GUCACGUGAGCCCCGCCCCCGCGCCGGCGCGCUCCGACGUGCCCUGUAACUUACCCUCCCUCAGAGGCCAGCCUGCGGGGACGGGCCGGCCGCGGCCGUAGCCGUGUGAACGCUCUUCGGGCUCGCGUCGUCGACCCGCAGCCGCGGGGCGGACUAAGAAGGGAGCCGCCUGCUGCGAGGCCGCCGGGCUCCCGGUUUAAAUGUGAUACUGGUGUAGAUCUCCUUGUUCUAAGCUAUAUUCAUCCAACAAGCCAUAAAGCCAUAAUGUGGUAUAACAUCCUUUUUGAGAGGUGAAUAUUAUUGAAUGAAAAUGGCUGACAGAAGUGGGAAGAUUAUUCCAGGACAAGUGUAUAUUGAGGUGGAAUAUGAUUAUGAAUAUGAAGCAAAGGACAGAAAGAUUGUGAUAAAACAAGGGGAGAGGUACAUCUUGGUGAAAAAGACCAAUGAUGACUGGUGGCAAGUCAAGCCAGAUGAAAACUCCAAAGCGUUUUAUGUGCCAGCCCAGUAUGUGAAGGAGGUCACGCGCAAAGCUCUCAUGCCACCUGUUAAGCAGGUAGCUGGUCUGCCAAAUAACUCCACGAAAAUAAUGCAGAGUUUGCAUCUUCAGAGAUCAACAGAAAAUGUGAACAAAUUGCCUGAGCUUUCAAGUUUCGGAAAGCCAUCGUCAUCUGUUCAAGGAACAGGUCUUAUUCGUGAUGCCAAUCAGAAUUUUGGACCCAGUUAUAAUCAAGGUCAGACUGUCAACCUAAGCCUGGACCUGACCCAUAAUAACGGAAAGUUUAACAAUGACUCACAUUCUCCUAAAGUUUCCAGCCAGAAUAGGACACGCUCAUUUGGUCAUUUUCCCGGUCCAGAGUUCUUGGAUGUAGAGAAAACUAGCUUCUCCCAGGAACAAUCUUGUGAUUCCGCAGGAGAAGGCUCUGAAAGAAUACAUCAAGAUUCUGAAUCUGGUGAUGAACUUAGCAGCAGCUCCACUGAACAGAUAAGGGCAACCACACCUCCAAAUCAAGGAAGGCCAGAUUCUCCUGUCUAUGCUAACCUUCAAGAACUGAAAAUAUCCCAGUCUGCUCUUCCCCCACUUCCUGGGAGCCCGGCAAUUCAGAUUAAUGGAGAAUGGGAAACUCAUAAAGACAGCUCAGGGCGUUGCUAUUACUAUAACAGAGGGACACAGGAAAGAACUUGGAAACCUCCUCGUUGGACUCGGGAUGCAAGCAUCAGCAAAGGAGAUUUCCAAAAUCCAGGGGAUCAAGAGCUUCUUUCAUCGGAAGAAAACUACUACAGCACUUCUUACAGCCAGUCAGAUAGUCAGUGUGGUUCUCCUCCAAGGGGUUGGUCAGAAGAGUUGGAUGAACGUGGGCAUACCUUAUAUACCAGUGACUAUACUAAUGAAAAGUGGCUCAAGCAUGUUGAUGAUCAAGGUAGACAAUAUUACUACAGUGCAGACGGAUCUCGGUCAGAAUGGGAAUUGCCAAAGUAUAAUGCUUCAUCCCAGCAGCAAAGAGAAAUAAUUAAAAGUAGGAGCCUGGACAGGCGGCUGCAAGAACCAAUAGUAUUAACAAAGUGGAGACAUAGCACCAUUGUAUUGGACACUAAUGAUAAGGAAUCUCCAACUGCCUCAAAACCCUGCUUUCCUGAAAAUGAGUCUUCUCCCUCCUCACCAAAGCACCAAGAUACAGAUCAAGAGAAAUAUGGAUUAUUAAAUGUAACAAAAAUUGCUGAAAAUGGGAAAAAGGUUCGAAAGAACUGGUUGUCUUCUUGGGCGGUGUUGCAGGGUUCAUCUUUACUUUUUACCAAAACUCAAGGAAGUAGCACAAGUUGGUUUGGCAGUAAUCAGUCCAAACCAGAGUUCACAGUGGACCUCAAGGGGGCAACAAUUGAGAUGGCUUCAAAGGAUAAAUCCAGCAAAAAGAAUGUAUUUGAGCUGAAAACUCGUCAAGGAACAGAACUGCUAAUUCAGUCUGACAAUGACACUGUUAUUAAUGAUUGGUUUAAAGUUCUUAGUAGUACAAUCAAUAAUCAGGCAGUAGAAACUGAUGAAGGAAUUGAAGAGGAGAUACCGGAUUCACCAGGAAUAGAAAAGCAUGAUAAAGAAAAGGAACAAAAGGAUCCCAAAAAGCUUCGUUCCUUUAAAGUAUCUAGCAUAGAUUCUUCAGAACAGAAAAAAACCAAGAAAAACUUAAAGAAGUUUCUUACACGACGCCCCACUUUGCAAGCUGUUCGUGAAAAAGGUUAUAUUAAAGAUCAGGUAUUUGGAUCCAAUCUCGCUAAUCUGUGUCAGAGAGAGAAUGGCACAGUACCAAAGUUUGUGAAGUUAUGUAUUGAACAUGUUGAAGAACAUGGUUUGGAUAUUGAUGGGAUAUACAGAGUAAGUGGCAACCUCGCAGUGAUCCAGAAACUAAGGUUUGCAGUCAAUCAUGAUGAGAAAUUGGACUUGAAUGACAGUAAAUGGGAAGAUAUUCAUGUCAUUACUGGAGCCCUCAAAAUGUUUUUUCGAGAAUUACCAGAACCUCUUUUUACAUUUAAUCAUUUUAAUGAUUUUGUUAAUGCAAUUAAGCAAGAACCAAGACAGCGAGUCGCUGCUGUUAAGGACCUAAUCAGACAGUUGCCAAAGCCAAACCAAGACACAAUGCAGAUUCUUUUCCGACAUCUCAGAAGAGUUAUAGAAAAUGGAGAGAAAAAUCGAAUGACCUAUCAGAGUAUAGCAAUUGUUUUUGGUCCCACUCUAUUAAAACCAGAAAAAGAGACUGGUAAUAUAGCAGUUCAUACUGUGUACCAGAAUCAGAUUGUAGAAUUAAUUCUUCUGGAACUGAGUUCCAUCUUCGGACGUUGAUUCUUACUGAAGACAACCUGUGGAAUAGAAGCUGGAUUCCAUCAGAUUUCAAAUGUUUAUACACAAUGUAUUUUAUUUUUUGGACCAAGCAGUGACUCUUUGAUUUUGCACUUUUUUUUUGAGGGAUCAGAAGGGAAGGGGAGAGUCGAGAUGUGUGUUAGGCCCUCAUAUUUGCUGCUUUGUUGCAAGUUGAUAUAACUGCGUGUAAUUAUGAAUUCAUUUUAUCCUGAAUGUUUGCAUUUCAUACUCUGAAUUUCAGUAAAAAUCAAAACUUAAAAUUCUAACCAGUCAUAUACACUGGAUAAUUUGGUAAGAAAACUGUAUUUUUUUUCCCUGAAAUUGGAUAAUGUACUUUCUUCUCAAGAUUCAUGACUUGAUAGAACAAUACUUUCAGUUAUGUUGCAAAGGCUCUUGGGCAUUUUAAACAAAAUGAAGUAUAUCCAUUUUGAAACCUGUGUAUUUCUUUUUCGGGGUUUCUGCAUGCAGUGGCAGUCUUAAGUGCCAAAAUUCAUUAUAACCCCAAAAUAACCCCUUGAUGAAGGCUUGCUGUCUUUUACUGUGUUACACAGCAUCCUUACUGGAUAUCUUAGUUGCUUGUUUGGGCAGCACACUAAUAUUACUUAAAACACUGUGAUAUACUGGAGUUUUAGUUAGCGGAAGUCAGUUCAGGGCAUUUUAGGGCUGUCUUGCUAUACUGAAUUGUAGCUAACAAUCCUAAUUAUAUCUAGUACCAUACUGAGUUAUUGGUAUGACCCUGUGGAAACACACAUUAUUUUAUGUAAAUAUAGGCUAAAGACUUAAUGUCCUUUAGCUUGUGUAUAUAAUUGUGUUGUAUAGUCUCAGAGUACAUUCUAACCCUACAUUUCUAAUCAUUGUUAUUGGUAAUCUUUUCUGUGAAUAUUAGGUUUCCUCCAGAAAUAGUCCGUUAUUUGGGAAAGUUAACUGUGUGCACUUUUAGAUAUUAACUACAUUUACAGGCAAAUCACUGUAAUGAGAAUGGUACUGGAAAAAUACUGAAUAGACUUGCUAAAUGGCACAUGCACUACAAGAGGAACCUUUUGGGUUAUUUAAUAUGUACAGAAAACAUUAGAAAAAAUUUAUUACAGAAUUCUAAUUCCAGUAUGAAUAGUGGAAACCCAUCUGUAAAUUAGAUGGAUGUUGGAUGGAAAAUGACAUUGCUAAAUUUGAGAAUUUCUUUUUACCUACUAAUGUAGAUUGCUUUGUAUAAUAAAACACAGGGUUUGGAAGGUUUUGUUACAGGGAGCAUGGUCUGUUGAAGAUUUUUAAAAUGUAUUUUUCUAGAUUAACUUCUGUACAUGAAAUGUCUAAUAAAACUAUAAGAGGUUUAGAGAUUUUUCCAUUGGAAAUGUGCAUUUUGGUUUCUAAUUUUUUUGUUUUUUCAUUUACUGGCAUACUGUUAUACCUCAUUUUUAAAAAUCAACUGAAUCCAAUAUUUCCUGUGGCAAAUAACACUUUCCUCAUUUCAUACCUUUUCUCCUCUCUUCCAUGCCAACAUUUCUCCACCCACAACGUACACUUUUUAUUUCUCCAUCAAUAUUUGAAAGCGAGUGAUUUGUGACCAGGAUUUUUUUUUCUUAGGGUUGCAUUUAUAAUUUACAGAUUGCCUUCCUUGGGAACAAGUAUUUUUUUGUAUGAUCUGUCUAAAAACCUCUCACCUGAAUUUUGUGGUAGAAAGUCUGUAUUUGUUGUUGUGAGCGUGUUAAAUUGAUAACAAACCAAACUACUUGAUAGCUAAAGCAGAUUGUUUCGGGUGGGGAGAAAAAGCCCUAAAUCAGAAUGUUUAUAUUUGCCUAAAGAUGUCCUUAAUAAUACAAUAUGCUUUAGAUCUUGCUUAUUUAGUGAUUGUAUACCAGGAAAACAAUUAGACUCAAAUCAGUGAUGUUCUUGUUCUUGGUGUUCAUGAACAUAUAUCAAAGAUUAAAAUUGUCCUGUGUUUCUUGUUUCAAGGUACGUGUGUGUGUGUGUGUGUGUGUGUGUGUGUGUGUGUGAAGUCUUAAAUGUUUUAUUAGUCUACAGCUAAUCAGUUUAUUGUAAUAUUGUAUGUACAGUGAGAUUAAUGUCUUGCGUUUUCAUCCUUUGUGAAUUAAAAAUUCUCACUUGUUUUGUAAUAACAAAGCUAGUAAUAUUUUCCUGUCUUGACAGCUUGGUUUUAUAGUAGAAAAUAUAUUAAAAGCUGAAAUAAAUUAUCAGUGGAAUUUUAUUUGUUAGUAAGUCUUCCUUCAUAAUGUCAUUGAAAAAG